GAACUCUUUUGUUCAACCAUGGCGAUGUCUGGAUCAGGGCAGCCUUGGAGGAUUUAUGGCCUCCAGUCUGGAGAAGGUAGGUGGGCUCGCAUUAUCUGUGUUGUAAGAAAAGUGUGUGAGGUCUUUGAGCCUAAGGCUGUCCAGGUAACAAAAGACUCUGUCAAAAAAAUAUGUCUAUUUAGAGUUCUUUGAGAGUAAUAUGUUGCUAUUUAUUUCACAUCUGUGUCGGGUAUUGAGCAUUUUCCUUGCUUUGCGGUUGUAACAAGAUCCUCAGCUUUCUUCCUUUUAAAGGUUGGGGAGCUAAUUUCUUGUAGGAAAUAACACAUUAAAUCCAAGCGUAUCACUAAAACAUGUGUGCCUUCUCUUUUUGCUCAAUUAAAAGAUUGAGCUGUUCGUGUUUUGUUUGAUAUGGGGGUACUUAUUGAACAUUGUCAACCUAAAGCAUUUUGAGUAACCAAGAGAAAAAUCAGGAUGGCCUAAUUCACUAAAAUUCCAAGUACAUUUGGGAUGUAUUUUUAUACUUCUUAAUUAUGAGAUUUUAAAUUGCUUUAUUUUUAAAGGUUGAGUGUGAGCUGAGUGUGUGUCUUUUUCUGUAGUCCUACCAUCCUUUCUGCAAAACUCAAGUGAAAAUUAUUUAUUUAGGAUGCCCUAUUGAGAUAUAGUGGAAUGUCUUUGUUUGCAUUUAUUCUUUUUCUGGGAUUUUGGUUAUAUCUAUAGCUGUAAAUAAAGGGGAAAGGAAGGCUUGGAGUGCAUGUUAGGACAAGAGGUCCCAAGUAGGAAAAAAAGUCUUGCCUUAGAGCUAUGCCUUGGGAAGUGCUUUUUAUUUAGUAACCUAAUCAGGACAUGCCUGUGUCUAUUUAUUGUUGGAUGAGCUUUUGAAGUACAUAUUGCCUGAAAGAGAAUUUUUCAAGUGGUUACCUAUUUUUUUUUUUUUCUCCUCUGGCUGGAGAAAAGUUAGAACAGAAGGGAACGCCGUGUAUUAUUUUUGUUGUUCUUCACUAAAGACAUAGUCUUGGCUACUUCGGAAAAAGAAGGAAGGUAUGAAAUGGUGGUUAAUCCUUUCCUCCAUUUUGUCCCCAAUUGCUUGCAGUGUCUCUUCACCCUAUCGAGAAACACUUUCUCAAAGCUGUCUCUGUACUGUGCUGAUAUCAGAGGAGUCAACUAAAAGUGAUUUUCUCUGUAGACAGUUAUUCUAGUUUAUGGGAUGUAUUAUAAAACUAUUGGGGAAAAUCACUGAACUACUAAGGUAAGGGAAAUAGCUUAAGGAUCUAUGAUCCAUAUUUGAAAUAGUCAUUAAGUUAUAUAAUUGGAUUUUUAGAGAACAAGAUAGAGCAGUUUCAGGAUGUAAGGUGUAAAAUAAAUCUGGUCCAUGAACUGCUUCCAAAUUGUCACCCUGACCAGAAGAAGUAACAUUCCUCAGGUUGUGGCUUUAUCUAGAAAGGGGAAAUGGCUAUUUCUGGAUUAGCUUUAUACAAAUGAGUGUAUUUCCCACCUGCUGCUUUUGCCUAGGGUUGGAAUUUUUCCUUUUCACUGCUUGUUACUUGGCGUUUGGAUGGAAACGUAUCCUCCCUUUCAGAGCCAGAAGAUUCUGUGUGAGUCAUCAAGAAAAAUUUCUCCGAGGAGUUAUUAAUUCAGUUAGUUGCUCCAUAGUAAAUGGUUCAUGCAACAGUGAUAAACCUCUGAAUUUGAAAUCUUUCUUUAAAAUCUUUUUUCCUUCAAAAAAUGCAUACAGUGGAUUGCUGAGCAUCUAAAAUCCCGCACUGUUCAGCACUGUCAUUCUUGGUAAUUGCUUUUUAGAGGAUUUGGUGGUGUUUUGCUGCUUAAGCUAAACCACGAAGUUAAACUUUUGUACUGUGGAAGUAGUUCAUGAAUCCUUUAGAUUUCUUGGAAGAGGAAAGAUGAGUGUGUGGUGAAUAUAUAUGAAUAUCGCAUAUUUGAAUGUGUUACUUACUAGUUUUGGUUGAGCAUUAAGGUUGCCCCUAAUGGAUGGGAUCUCUGCCAGGGGUAACUCUUGGAGUCCUAGGUGCUAUUGGGGAGGAACCUUUCAUUCUCGGCAUUCUGGGGGAGAUUUACAUCUGUAAGCCGGAUAAAAAUAUGUGGAAAGGUGAUUAGUUUAAUUGGCCCACUAUUAUAAUUAUUCAGUAGGAGGUGGCUGUGGGACUGCUAUUAUAGCCCAAAAUGCCUGGUAGGAAGAGGCGGAGACUCAUUGAAAACAGCAGCAAGGUUAUAAAACGUUGGUUUAAACGUGCAUUUAAUAACAGAUUACCCUGGUGCUUUAAAGACAGAGGAAUGCUUAAGUAUUUGGUACAAGAAUCCAUCCAAAAAAAGACGCGGAUUUUUUUUCAAAGAUAAUUGUGGGAAAUUCUGCUAAUGAUUUCUUUUCCCUUAAAAUAUCAUACAGGGGAGUAGGAUUUAGGUAGGUGUAAAGUUGCUCAACGUGUUGGUAACUUUAAGAUUAUUUCUUCUCUGGUUGUUGCCACAGACACUCAGGGUGGCCACAAUGGUGGUGUUGUUUUAGGCUUCUUUCAAAAAAGAAGUCCAGUCCAGGAUAAUGUUGUAAAGUGGAGUAUUUUUCUUUCACAUCAAAGGGCAAGGAAUGUUUUACAGACAGUGAGCUAAGAAGUAGGGCACAGAUAUUUCAGUACUUGCGUUGGGAAACUAUGUGUGGAAUGUCAUAGUUCAUAUACCAGAGACCCCGAAGUGAAUCCAGGUGCCUGCACGGUGCUGACUUUUCCUGGAGUGAGAUGACUGUAGGCAGAAAUUGCAGCCAGAUGAACCUAAAAUAAAAUUGAUGGCUUUAUUGGACAUUCUUUUCAUGAGAUUUAACUUCUUAACGUGCACAUACAUCACUCUGGGGAUGUCAUUAUCAUGGCUGACCUUUCGUUUGGGGGAGCUGCUGCUCGCUGUCUGUGCAGCUCCGAUCAGCUUGGCUUUGAUUACCACCCACAUCUGUUGAGCAUGUGAGAGAGAGAUUUUGAAAAAUCUCAAGCACACUGACAACUGGCUACAAAGAUUUAAUUAAGACCGGUCAGAACUAAUUUCAGUUAUAUAUUCCAGUUUAGGGUAUCAACUCCUCUGGUUUCAGAAGGGGGAGUUAUGACUUCCUAAAAGUUGUUGUUGAAGGCAGCAUGAGGAAAUCUCCUUGGGCAAGCAGUGGGUUUCUUUGUCCUAGCUCCCCCACUGCUACCUGGGGUUAAUGAUUGCAGGGUGGCUGGCGUAAUGAACCAGUGCCGGAAAGCUUAUUAUCAACAUGCUGAAGUCAUAUUUAGAAAUCAUUCCUCCUCCUUUUUUCUCCUUUCCAAUACAAGUCAGAGCACUGCUGUGGUUCCACCUAAUAAAUACUGCAGGCUUCAUUGGGCUGUUCAAUGAGACCUAAUAUAGUAUCAUUUGUGCACUUUAGUGGGUGGUUCCUAUUUAUAUUUUUGUGUGGUUUACUGCUCAAUCUUGGGAAGAUGUGGGGUUUGAGGGUUUAUCAGUUGCAGUUUUUUGUGGAACCAGUUUGAGUGAGACAAGACUUUGGCCAUUAUUUGUCGGGUUACAUGGAUCUCCAUAUGAGCUAUGAAGAUACUGGAAUAAUUGGGUCACAAUAAUGUAAAAUCGUAGUCUGUACUUUCAGCUCAUUCCAGAGGAAUGAUUGGAAGCCCUGCUCUCCCUCUCUUCUGCAUGCAAACCUCAGGUGUGAUUUCGGCCUGUGCCCAAGUGUUCUUGAAAUGUUCAAGGCUGUCCGUUCCCACUCUGUGAUGAGGCUUCCGGUUGAUGUGUGACAUCACUUAGGGCAGGAACUGGCACUGUCUUGAUCCUGGCUGUCCUAGAGAAGCUUCUGUGCUUGGCCUUGGGAAGCCACCCCAUUUGGUGCUGCUGUAGUCUCCUUUCUGCUCCUCUUUUAACAGCUGCCUCCCACCUGUGCUCACUUCCACCUGCAGGCCUUGUUUUCCAGUGGCACUGGAGUGCCAUGCUGAGGUCACUGGACAAGUUCCUUAUCAGAGCCCCCUUCCCAUUAGAGUGAGGCUGCACCCCAUCCUGCCUGGGCUUACUUUGUGCGUUGCUUGGGGGCAUGGAGAAGGUUCUUGCCCUUGCUGCUUUAUAUGAGGUCCAAUUCCUCCAGUGUUUGCCAUCUCCUUUAGAGCUCUCUGGUGACAAAACCUUCUUCAGCUUGUCUACCCUCCAGGCUGGUGAGUUGAACUCAGACUGGUGCUCGGAAAGGUUAAAGGACUUGUCCAAGAUGUUACCUUACUGGCAAACUGCAUUCCCAAGUCUUUAUUGAUCUCCGAGGGCAUCUCUUAAUUUGUUGGAGUUUUCUUUUCCUGGAAAAAAUACUGCUUGGGUCUCAGUUUCUCCACAUAUAAAAUCAGAAUAAGACCAUAAAUUCAUGUAGUUGAAAGGGGCGGUUUCAGGAAGAAAACUAAGAUAAUGAAAGCCUCCGGAAAAGGGUCUGGGACGACAUUAUUUACAGAGUACUUUCCACACAUUGUCAGGGUGGGGCCGCACAGGAACCUUGUGGGGUAGGCAUCAUUGACCUGUUUCAAAAAUGAACAAAGUCAGUCCCAGAGACCUUGAAUGGAGGCUUAUCAAAGCUAAGCAUACGGCUUCAAGUUUAACCGUCAAAUGGUAGAGUUAGUCAUGGCUUUUGGAUGUGCGGGCCAGGCAUGGUGCAGGGCCAGGUAUGUUUUAGCCUUGUGGUUCUUUUCCUGAUAUUUCGGUCCUGUGGGCCUCCCCAAAGUGGCUUUGCACCUAUGUUUGUUAUGGGCAUAAGGAAGUUAGAAUUCUAUGAAUAUGUACUGAUUUUUUGUGAUUCUGAAUUUAAAUAGGCCUCUAUAAAGCUAAUACUUGAAGUUUUGUUGUAAUGAAGCAUCACAAAUACUUUUACAUAGGAAAAAGGACCAAGCUGAUCUCCUUAAAGCGGUUGCAAAAACCACCCAGUUGUUAUACGAUUGUUUGUUUCAUGUUUCUUGUUAUGUGGCAUAUUUCCAGUAAGUGGAGGGACCAAAUAUUUUAUAGUUACAGAAACUUCUUCUCUCCCUCCUUGAAGUUUAAAAAAGUGGAUCAAAUGUCUGCCUAUUUUCAAGGAGGCAGGGAGACAGAAGAUCUUUUCCAGAUUGCAGGAAGGCCAACGCAGGUUGCACCCAGAGAACUAUGGAAACCACUGUUGAGGAGGAAGGAAUUGGGUGAAAAUUAAAGAAUCAAGCUAGUAAAAGUGAAAAGAGGCCUUUGGUUUUUUUUUUUGGACAGUUUUUAAGGGCCUUCAUAAAUACUUGGUGUACUCCUCAAAGACCAAGCGUUGAAGGGUUAAGUCAGGGAACUAAAACUUGGAUUGUGUGUUGACCCCUGUGUAGCUGUGGCCAGGGCUCCUGAUUUUCCCCUGACGAUCCAUUGGUAGAACAAGGCCAGUGGUACUGUUUUCUGGUGCAGGGGAGGCUCGGACCUGCAGGGGAGUUACGGAGGCUGGCCACUGGUUUGGAGCAGACAGGUAAGUAGCCUCUAGGGAGGUGGUAGCUCUGUACAACAGUCUGUUCCCAAUGUCUGGGUGACUCUUGUUCCCAAUACUUGGCUCUCUUUUUGGAUGUCAGAGUCAUAUUCUUCAUUCUCCAUGUCUCCUGCUAAUUUUUGGCAUUGACCCAUCCAGGAUUUAUUUCAGCAGCUAGCAUGGUGCCUGACCUAUCCAUAGUAGGUGCUUAGUAAAUACUGCACUCCACAGGGGGAAGAGGGCAGGCACGUUCUGCCUAUUGACGUGGUGGGAAGAGAGACCGUGCUUAGGGACAGGUUUGGGAGCUUCAUUAUUUCUGCCUUGGGACUGUUUGAAUGCACCCUAUUUUGCUAUAGGGGAAACACUGCAAUAACAUAAAUCCCACUUGAAUCAUUCUUUGUUCUAUCACCCCUGCCCUUAUCACUGCUCUUGUAAGACAGACAUCAUAGGAGACUCCUAAUCCUCUCCCUGCCUCUGGUGGGUGCAUGACACUGAUCUAGCUUCCACUUGCACAGUUCUCUCUCUCUCUGCCCCUAAAACAGAAAUAUGAUCAUGUUAUUCUCCUACUUACAUGCCCGUCAGUGGCUCCCCAGUGCCGUACUGCUGUGGCACACAGAACCCUACGUGAUCUGGUCCUGCGUGCUCUGUAAGUGGCAAGUCCCAGGGCCUCUUCGUGCAGGCUGUUCAAGGGGGUCUCAUAACCUACCAGUCCGAGUUAGACUUGUUGAGUCUUAAAACCAAGCUGCUUUGAGUUGGGUCUUCAGAUGAACUGGGAAUCAACAUAUUUGGGAUGGAUCUGUAGGGUGCAUUUAAAAGGCACUGAAUGUUUGGAAUGGAGUGCAAGAAUUAAUGUUAAGUUACCAGAGAAAAUUGAGGUAUUAAGGGAUCUGCGCAUAUAGUUUUCAAAAAUCAAUUAAACAAAAAGCCUGUUUUUUAACUGAUUCUAUAGUUCAUUUGGAAGACUAUGUAUAUUACAUUAUAUCAUAUAUCUACAUGUGUGAUAUAUUUAUAAUAGAAAAAUGAAGCAGAAACUUCUACUACCAAAUAUUAAAACACAUUAUAAAGUGCUGAUAAAAGAUGAUGAUGUGGGCAUAAAAACAUGCAAAUAAUCCAACAAAAUAGCACUUUUCAAAACUUUUUUUAGCGUAUGGAAUAACUUAAUUAUAAGUCGUUGGGGAAGGAACAGAUUAUUUGAUGAAGGGGGUUGUGAAAUUGGGUAUUUUAAAAAAUCUAUUUAUAUCUUUGCUUUGGUGACACACCAAAAUAUCUUUCAUACGGAUUGGAUUUAAGUAUAUAUAUUUAAAGCUCUAAGCGAGAAAAAAAAUGUGGAGAAAAUUUGAUCUCUGAGAAAGAGGAUUUUUUUUAAGCCUAAAAGCCAAAAACUCUAAGUGAUUGCUCAACUUAAGUACAUAACAGUAUUCAUUUUACUGAAGAAUUACAAAUAACUAAUAAUGAUCACUAGAACAGAAAAAUGUCAAAAGAAAAAACACACGGUAUUCAUUGUCCUCUCAUAAAAUUAAGAAAGAUUUAGAAAAUGCAAAUACUCAGUGCUCAUAACAAUAUGGUUAGAUUUUCAACACUUUCUAAAAGGAAAAAUGUUAAAAUAAAUUCCAAAGAAAAAAUUUUUUAAAUGGUUUGGUUUUUACAUAUACUGGGGAAACUUACUAUUUAAAGACUAGAGUUAAUUAUUUCAAAAUAAAAAUAGUCUUUCUAAUUUUAGUUUCAUAAUGUUGUUUUUUAAUCUUUGUUUGAUUUUAAACAACCUUUUAGUCUUUGGGCUGUCCAAAAUUAUAAAUUAUAUGUCUGUAAUUUACUAUUGUUAAUCAUACAGUUCUCCAUAUAAAAAAUGGCAGAGAGAAAAACUGGAAAAAUAUGCCCUGUGAAGGGGAUUUAUGAUCCUUAAUAUCCCAGAAGAAGACCAUAAUGAGGCAUCUUAUGUAACAGAGAAGUCAUAUAGGGCUUCAGUUUCUAAAGUGCUCAAAUUUUAAUUCAUAGUGUGACUUUGAACAGGCUACUUUACCUCUCUUGGUCUCAGUGUCUUCAUCUGUGAAAUGGGAGGGUUGGGUUAGAUCAGUUUCCCAGCUGAGAUGCCCCGGCACAGCUGUGCCAAAAUUCUGAUGCCCCUCGGCCCUAAAGACAGCUGGACAGAGCUGGGGUGGAGGCCCUAGGUCAGUUACUUCCACCCAAGGGCAGCCAUUUGUUUUUCCCAAGGAAAAUAGUACCACAAAUCACUCUCAAUGCACUCUUAGAUAAUGAGUUGUCUUACUUUUAAAUUCAAGAGGUGAGAGCUACAUGGAAGAGGAGAUAAUUUUGGACAUCACAGUGAACCAUUCGUCCUUCCCAGUCAAUAUUCAAUAGGUAUGUUAAAAAAUGAAUGGAAGAAAACACAUCAAAAUGUUAUUAGUAAUUAUCUCUGGUGAUUGACUUACAGGUAAUUUUUAUUUGCUUAUUUAUAAUAUUCCGCCUCAUUCAAAUUUACUGUUAAGAAUUUGUUAAAUUUAAAUAAGAAAAGUUAUUUAAAACAAAUCCCAACCUGUACCCAUUUUUACAUUUAAAAACUCCAUGAGUACGAGUGACGGCUAUGGCUGUCAGAGUUAAGAAUCUAACAAAAAUAAAACGGCAAACAUGGACCCAUUUCACAUUAUGGAAAUAUCCUGGGAUAUUUUCAUUCCAAGGUUUCUUGCUCAGUGCUUACUUUCAAGGCUGGUUUCAGGUGUGAGGAAGAAGCUUUGAGCAGAAGGCCUGUUUGUAGAGUGAGUGAGUAGCCUUCUUACUUGGGGCAGCUGACCCCAAAGGUCUUCCUCUCCAUCUCCCUCCUUCAGUGCUUUCUUCCCUUAUUUUUCCCCUUCCCUGUGACCCCUGAAUUGCUGAUAAUUCCUUUCCUUCUUUGUUCUUCUCAAUCCCUGGUGUGUAUAUGGUUAGAAGUUCCGGUGCCCACUUAGCUGAGCCACAGAGAUUCCAUUUUUAACUGGUCCCUCAUAUGCCAGCCCAUCUAGUUCCUCAGGCAUUACCGCCUUCCCUCUCCCAGCUUUAUUCUGCUUAUUUACAUCUUUCUGGGAAUGAUGUGCUUCAAACUUUCCAACCUAUUAGUUUAAACCAGAUUUAGUGGCAGGGGCGGGGGGAAGUAGACUUUCUCUGCCCUUUGGUUUUGCUUUACUUUGAGAUAAACACUAUAUACAUUAAAGGUGCUUAAAUGAUGUUUUCUCUGACUUCCUAAAGGGGUUACUUUUCAUUGACUCCUAACAUUUUAAUUCUCUGAUUGUGAUUGUUUUGUCUAAAUCAUGGGGUGGAGUGCAUGUGGGGAAUUAGAAAACUAAUUGUCAUUAUAACCUUUCAGCAGAAUUUUGGAAUGAUUAAUAGCUAUGUUAAUAUGCCAUAACAUAAUUACUUAUAAAAAUCAGAAUAUACCACCACCUUGUUAGUAUUAAAAUGGUGCUAGGCUGGGCGCGGUGGCUCACGCCUGUAAUCCCAGCACUUUGGGAGGCCCAGGCAGGUGCAUCACCUGAGAUCAGGAGUUCGAGAUCAGCCUGGCCAACAUGGUGAAACCCCGUCUCUACUAAAAAUAUAAAAAUUAGCUGGACGUGUUAGCGGGUGCCUGUAAUCCCAGCUACUUGGGAGGCUGAGGCAGGAGAAUUUCUGGAACCCAGGAGGCAGAGGUUGCAGUGAGCUGUGAUCGUACCAUUGCACUCUGGCCUGGGAGACAGAGUAAAACUCUGUCUAAAACAAAACAAAACGAAACAAAAAAACCUGCUAAAAUAUAAGUUACUUUCUUUAUAUAACAUUUUAGGACCUUACAGUGUACCUUAACUUUCUGAGCAUAGAUAACAAAUGAAGAUAAUAAGAAAUAUUGUUUUAUAUUGUUUAUAAAGCACUGUGCCCUACAUUGCAGUUUAUAGAACCACAUAACAGUUGGCCAUGGGCAGUAUCUCAGGAAGCCUUAAAAUCUCGGGAAGACUGACAGAAUGGCGGAGCUAAGAUGGACCUCAGGGUCAUCUAAUCCAGUGUUUCCCAACCAUUUUCACAUCAUGGCACACAUUGAAAAGGUGCACAGCACACCCUGGGGAAAUAAAUGACUGCUCUUGGCUGGAGGUAGUGGAUCUGAGGACUCCAGCCUAGGCUGUGUCCAGCUCCCCUGAGGGCUGAUGGGCAUCAGAACCUUGGCGCAGCUGUCCUGGGGCAUUCCAGUUGGGAACUGUGAUCUAACCCAACCCUGCCAUUUUACAGAUGAGACACAUCUGCAUUUACAUAUCGAGACCCAGAGAGGUAAAGUAGAUUGUUCAAGGUUACACAGUGAAUUAGUGACAUUAUGAUAAAUAGAAUUUGAGCAUUUCAGAAACUGGAGUUUAAUAUAACUUCUCUUUUACAUUGCAUGCCUCAUUAUGUUGUUCUUACAGUACAUUAGAACUUUUAUAGGGCACGUUUUUCCAAAAGGUUUACCUCUGCCAUAUUGUAUAUGGAGAAGUAUGAUUAAUAUUAGUAAAUUAUAGAUAUAUCUCUUUUGGACAACCUAAAGAAUAAAAGGCUCUUUUAAACCCCAAAUUCAAGUUAAAAAUUAAGAUUACGAUGCUAAAAAUAGUCUAACAUAUGUAAAAAUGAUUUAAAAAAUUUUAUUUACACAAAGAAUGUACUCAGGCUAUGAAACUUGUAUGCUGGCAGUUGCCUCACUUUAAAAAAUAAAAGAGAGAAAAGUAAGAUGGAAAAGAAAAUUAAAAUUGUAAACAUUUUAAUGACUCACCACUACCUCCAUCCUUAGAUUUCUUUGCCAUCAACUAUUUAAACCCUUUAAGAAUAUUAGGAAACCGUGGUUACUUGGCGUGGUUUUAUAAAUCUGUUCUGGUAAUCUCUAAAUUCUCCUUCAACCCCAUGAUGAUUCACUGAUUCUAGUGUAAUGAGGGCUUGGUUCAGCCUUACAUAUAUUUAUGUGUGUGUCAACCAAGAUGUACAUGGGAACAUGGCAUCUCAUCUUCAGUUCUUUGUCUGAACCACAAAAUUUAUGUGCCAAUUCAGGACAGUUUAUGGCGCUAGGUUUGUAACAUCAGAGUGACUUGUUCCACCAUGACCUCAAGAUGGUAGCUGUAGACUAGCGACACCUUCCAUUAACAGCUGGUUGACCUUGGAGAAGUUCUAUAAUCUCUUUUUUUGCCUCUGUUUUUUCAUCUGUGAAGUGAAGGACAGGCUGCCUACCUGCUAGGAUUGUUAUAUGGAUUAAAUGCAUUAGUUAGUGCAAAGUCUUGAACAACACCCAGUGCACACAGAAAUAAAUAUGAUAAAUAAGUACAGUGAAUGUGGGCCGUUUUCAUCACCAUUAUUAGUAAUAGCUGCCAUGAGUUGUCAUUGAACAGGGAGCAGUAAGGGGGCCUCCAGGUAUAAACAAGACCCACCCUGCUUUGUCAGUCUCAGGUUUUAUAAAAAUAGUCGCUGCCUAACUGAGUUCUUGGGGCACUAAGGAAUAGGAUUAUUAUUACCAGAUGCCCCUGAGUCUCUCUGCUUAUUGAGGCGUUUUUUUUUUUUUUUUUUUUUUUGGUAGGGCUUUGUUUGGGAAAAAAAAGAAAGAAAAUCUACCUCCAGGGACAUGGGUAAAAUAUUUUUUCCCUUAGUUAACGUUAAAUUCCAGUCAUUCUUUUGCAGAAGUGUUGUGGAACAGAAGGGAGGGGUAAAGAUUCCAACUUUAGACAUUAGACUAAGAAUGCAUGUAAUGAGUACCCAGACAGCAUGACACUUUUUCAGUUAUCACUGCCACCCCCAUCCCCCCAAAAAAACACACUGUGAGGGAAAGAGCAAGAGCUGUGAACUCAGACAGGCUGAGUGCAGCCCCUAGCCCGCACUUAAUGGCUGAGUACAUCCGGGCUAUGCAUUCACCUUCUCUGAUGGGUCUUCUAGGUUGGAGUCAUCUUCUAGAGGUGCUGUAAGCUGGUGUAAGAGACUAGCAAAGUGCCAGCAGCAUAGGCCCUGUGCCCUAAAUGGGCCCACAUUUUUCUGAGUUCAUCUUUGCUAAAGGGAUUUUUUUUCUUAAGUACAUACUGUAUCCAGAAUUGGUGGGUUCUUGGUCUCACCAACUUCAAGAAUGAAGCCGCAGACCCUUGCGGUGAAUGUUGUAGUUCUUAAAGGCAGCGUGUCCAGAGUUUGUUCCUUCUGAUGUUUAGAUGUGUUUGGAGUUUUUUCCUUCUGGUGGGUGCUUGGUCUCGCUGGCUUCAGGAGUGAAGCUGCAGACCUUCGUGGUGAGUGUUACAGCUCAUAAAGGUGGUGUGGACCCAAAGAGUGAGCAGUAGCAAGAUUUACUGCAAAGAGCAAAAGAACAAAGCUUCCACAGUGUGGAAGGGGGACCCGAGCAGGUUCCCACUGCUGGCUUGGGCAGCUUGCUUUUAUUCUCUUAUCUGGCCCCACCCACAUCCUGUUGAUUGGUCCAUUUUACAGAAAGCUGAUUGGUCUGUUUUAUAGAGAGCUGAUUGGUCUGUUUUGACAGGGUGCUGAUUGGUGCGUUUACAAUCCCUGAGCUAGACACAAAAAUUCUCUAUGUCCUCACUAGAUUAGCUAGACACAGAGCACUGAUUGGUGCAUUUGCAAACCUUGAGCUAGACACAGGGUGCUGAUUGGUGUAUUUACAAUCUCUUAGCUAGACGUAAAGGUUCUCCAAGUCCCCACCAGAUUAGCUAGACACAGAGUGCUGAUUGGUGCAUUCACAGACUCUGAGCUAGACACAGAGUGCUGAUUGGGGCAUUUACAAACCUUGAGCUAGACACAGAGUGCUGAUUGGGGCAUUUACAAACCUUGAGCUAGACACAGAGUGCUGAUUGGUGUAUCUGCAAUCCCUUAGCUAGACAUAAAGGUUCUCCAAGUCCCCACUAGACUCAGGAGCCCAGCUGGCUUCACCCAAUGGAUCCUGCACUGGGGCCACAGGUGGAGCUGCCUGCCAGUCCUGCUCGGUGUGCCCGCACUCCUCAGCCCUUGGGCAGUAGAUGGGACCAGGUGCCAUGGAGCAGGGGGCGGCGCUCGUUGGGGAGGCUUGGGCAUGGCGGGCUGCAGGUCCUGAGCCCUGCCCCGCGGGGAGGCAGCUGAGGUCCGGUGAGAAUUCGAGUGCAGUGCCGGCGGGCCAGCACUGCUGGGGGACCCAGUGCACCCUCCGCUGCUGCUGGCCCGGGUGUUAAGCCCCUCACUGCCCGGGGCCGGCGGUGCCCACUGGCCGCUCAGAGUGCGGGGCCUGCCGAGCCCACGCCCACCUGGAACUCACUCUGACCUGCAAGCGCCGUGCGCAGCCCCGGUUCCUGCCUGUGUUUCUCCCUCCACACCUCCCUGCAAGCUGAGGGAGCUGGCCCCAGCCUCGGCUAGCCCAGAAGGGGGCCCCCACAGUGCAGUGGUGGGCUGAAGGGCCCACCUCUCGAACGUGGCCAGAGCGGACGCUGAGGCUGAGGAGGUGCUGAGAGCAAGUGAGGGAUGCGAGGGCUGCCAGCACGCUGUCACCUCUCAAUACUUUAGGCAAUUUCUUGUGGUGGCACAUUUGAGACUGUUUCAUGCCAGUGGCUUUUCCAUUUUCCUUUCUUUUUUUGAGACUCUUGCUCUGUUGCCUAGGCUGGAGUACAGUGAUGCGAUGAUAACUCACUGUAACUUCAAACUCCAGGGCUCAAGCGAUCCUCCCACCUCAGCCUCCUGAGUAGCCAAGACUAUAGGCGCAUACCACCAUACCUGGCUAUUUUUUUUUUAUUUUUUGUAGAGACGAGGGCUCGUCAUGUUGCCCAGGCUGAUCUCAAACUCCUGGACUCAGCCAGUCUUCCUACCUCGGCCUCCAAGAGUGCUGGGAUUCCAGGCAUGAGCCACUGUGCCUGGCUGGCCUUUUCACUUUCUAUUAAUGGUUCUCGGGGUCAUCUCCCGCUGCCCUUCUCCCCCAGGAAUAUUUUAGCAGCAUUCUAAGUUAUUUCAGCUCCUUCAGUUUUGUUGCUCAUAUCUUUGCUACCCUUGCUCACCAUUACAAUUCAAAGCCUCACUGUUCUUGCUUUCUCACUGAUGGGUUAACCUUUUUUUCUUCUAUCACAAAUAGGGUUGCUAGAUAAAAUAUUGGGCACCCAGUUAAGAUGGAAUUUCAGAUAAAUGCCAAACAAUUUUUUUUUUUUUUCGAGUCAGAGUCUCCCUCUCUAGCCCAGGCUGGAGUGCAAUGGUGCGAUCUUGGCUCACUGCAACCUCCGCCUCCCAGGUCCCAGUUCAAGCAAUUCUCCUGCGUCAGCCUCCGAGUAGCUGGGAUUACAGGCAUGUGCCACCACGCCCAGCUAAUUUUUGUAUUUUUAGUAGAGAUGGGGUUUCACCAUGUUGGCCAGGCUGGUCUUAGACUUCUGACAUCAUGAUUCGCCCGCCUUGGCCUCCCAAAGUGCCGGGAUUACAGGUGUGAGCCACUGUGCCCGGCCCCAAAUAAUUUUUUAGCCUAAGUGUGGCCCAUCCACUAUUUGGGACAUACUUAAACUAAAAAUUAUUUGUUUAUCUGGAAUUCAGAUUUAACAGAGCAUCCUGUAUUUUUAAGUCUGGCCACUCUACAAAUAUCUGUACCAAUUCUCCCAUUACAACUUUUUACCCACACGGCAGCAUGUUUUGGCCAAGAGGAAUAAAAGAGGCUUCUCAGAUAUUUCCUAAGGCCCUGUUUUGACGAACUUAAAGAGAAAAUGCCGACAGGUUAAUAGGAGAUUCUGACAACGAAGAGGAAUUCCUGUGAUUUUAGGGGUAGAGAUAUAUAUCGACUUCGAUUUGGGAGAUCACUUGGUAAAUGUGAGGUGUCUGUAUUUUGGGCUGAAUGUCAACUCUGGAAGUAGGUAAAAGUUAAGUUUUAUAUCCACAUGCUAUUCCACCUCCGUUCAAAACUUAGAAAAAUAUUGUCUUCCAUACCUAAUUCACAGUCCUAAUGAUCAGGUAUUAGCUGAACAGAACAAAGAAGCCUGCCUUAGAGGAUGUUGUGAAUGGGUUUUGGGGAUGGAGACUUGAGACACAAUAUAAAAAGAUGGUCAGACCAGUUAAGUAUGACAUGAGGCAGUUUUAUGAAACGUAAAAAUGGCUUUUUCAUGCAGCUCAGAGGCAUGGAUAUAGAAAGGGAAAAACCAAAAAGAAAUGAUUUGUGUAUGUCAGCCCACUAACAUUUUUGGAAAUGUGCCUGAGGACUACCGAAGUAAUCAGAUGACAUGGACUUGCCCCUUGAGGAAUUUAAUUUAUGGGUGAGAAAUUUGAAAAGAAAGUGGCUUAUCCUAGCUUUUCUUUUUUUUUUUUUCCUUUUGUUUCUUCCAAAAAUUUUCUCCCAAGGGACAGAAGUGGGUCUGCCACAGCUAUGGAUAGGAAUAACCAAGUGAAGGGAGGCAGUGACGUGGGUACUUCCACAUAGAGGCUGCACUCUGAUGAUUCAGGAAUAUUUCUUGAGUACCCUUUUAUUUUAUUUUAUUUUAUUUUAUUAUUUUGAGACAGGGUCUUGCUCUGUUGCCCAGGCUGGACUGCAGUAGUGCGACCUUUGCUCACUGUAGCCUCAACCUCUAUGGCCCAAGGGAUCCUCCCACCUCAGCCUCAACAAGUAGCUGAGACUACAGGUGUGUGCCACCAUGCCUGGCUAAUUUUUCUAAUUUUUGUAGAUACGGGGUUUCACCAUGUUGCCUAGGCCAAUCUCCAACUCCUGGACUCAAGCAGUCCCCCUCCCUUGGCCUCCCAAAGUGCUGGGAUUACAGGCAUGAGCCACUGAGUUGAGUACCUUUUAGGUGGAUUGUCAUCAUAUUUGAGUGCCUAGCAUGGUGUUAGGUGCUGGGGAUGUAGCAACAGUCAGCAAGGGCAGAGUCUCAGUCAGCUCUGUAGAGCUUGUGUGCUGUCAUCAUAGGUACUUUGAGAAAUGCAAAGGUAGACCAGGUAGGAUAGGGAAUUCUGGCCUCUAGGAGCUUCCUUAGGGUUGAUUACCUAUGCUUUUCCUUCUGUGGCAAUUGGAGACUCAGUCUGCUGUUGGCCAGAAUACUGGAUAACUGGCAGGUAACUCUGCAUUGUUAGGAAGGCUGAUCAGACUUCAGGUCCCCCAUUGAGGAGUUUUACAUCUGAAUCUUCAGCAGCUGGUCUAAACUGACAAUGGCAGGCUUCAGUAAAAUCAGCCAUUCAAUUUAUCUAUAUUAUAAAAUGAUGAAGGCAUGCUCCAUCUGGUAUCAGAUAGAGUACCUUCUAAUAUUGGUGCAUUAUCAGUACCUUUGUGUGUAGGGGGUCUGCUGUAAUGAAAAACAGUAGAGCUCGAUUCAUCCUAAUUACAUUUUGAGCAAUUUUAGGGGGCUGAAAAGAUUGUACUGUGACAAUAAGGUUUUUCCUUCUUACCAAAAGAAUUUAUAAAUGGUACAGAAAAUGAAAGAUGGCUAGUGGUUUUAGCAGUUCUAAUGUUUUUUCUUUUUUUAGAUAAGGAAAAAAACCCCACUCUGAUUCUAAAACCCGCUGGAAUUUGAACUGUUGCCUGUGUUCUGAAAGUGUCUUGAAUUGCUUGGGAUCCCAAGCCUGAAGUUUACAGCAUCUCAUGGUGUCCAGAGAGCAGAGCUGACAUCUGAUAAAGACAUGUACCUUGACAACAGCUCCAUUGAAGAAGCUUCAGGAGUGUAUCCUAUUGAUGACGAUGACUACGCUUCUGCGUCUGGCUCGGGAGCUGAUGAGGAUGUAGAGAGUCCAGAGCUGACAACAUCUCGACCACUUCCAAAGAUACUGUUGACUAGUGCUGCUCCAAAAGUGGAAACCACGACGCUGAAUAUACAGAACAAGAUACCUGCUCAGACAAAGUCACCUGAAGAAACUGAUAAAGAGAAAGUUCACCUCUCUGACUCAGAAAGGAAAAUGGACCCAGCCGAAGAGGAUACAAAUGUGUAUACUGAGAAACACUCAGACAGUCUGUUUAAACGGACAGAAGUCCUAGCAGCUGUCAUUGCUGGUGGAGUUAUUGGCUUUCUCUUUGCAAUUUUUCUUAUCCUGCUGUUGGUGUAUCGCAUGAGAAAGAAGGAUGAAGGAAGCUAUGACCUUGGAGAACGCAAACCAUCCAGUGCUGCUUAUCAGAAGGCACCUACUAAGGAGUUUUAUGCGUAAAACUCCAACUUAGUGUCUCUAUUUAUGAGAUCACUGAACUUUUCAAAAUAAAGCUUUUGCAUAGAAUAAUGAAGAUCUUUGUUUUUUGUUUUCAUUAAAGAGCCAUUCUGGCACUUUAAUGAUAAAAUCCCAUUGUAUUUAAAACAUUUCAUGUAUUUCUUUAGAACAACAUAAAAUUAAAAUUUAACAUCUGCAGUGUUCUGUGAAUAGCAGUGGCAAAAUAUUAUGUUAUGAAAACCCUCGAUGUUCAUGGAAUUGGUUUAAACUUUUAUGCGCAAAUACAAAAUGAUUGUCUUUUUCCUAUGACUCAAAGAUGAAAGCUGUUUCAUUUGUGUCAGCAUGUCUCAGAUUGACCUUACCAAGUUGGUCUUACUUUGUUAAUUUAUCUGUUGUCCCCUUCCUCUCCUCUGCCCUCCCUUCUUGUGCCCUUAAAACCAAACCCUAUGCCUUUUGUAGCUGUCAUGGUGCAAUUUGUCUUUGGAAAAUUCAGAUAAUGGUAAUUUAGUGUAUAUGUGAUUUUCAAAUAUGUAAACUUUAACUUCCACUUUGUAUAAAUUUUUAAGUGUCAGACUAUCCAUUUUACACUUGCUUUAUUUUUCAUUACCUGUAGCUUUGGGCAGAUUUGCAACAGCAAAUUAAUGUGUAAAAUUGGAUUAUUACUACAAAACCGUUUAGUCAUAUCUAUCUAAUCAGAUCUUCUUUUGGGAGGAUUUGAUGUAAGUUACUGACAAGCCUCAGCAAACCCAAAGAUGUUAACAGUAUUUUAAGAAGUUGCUGCAGAUUCCUUUGGCCACUGUAUUUGUUAAUUUCUUGCAAUUUGAAGGUACGAGUAGAGGUUUAAAGAAAAAUCAGUUUUUGUUCUUAAAAAUGCAUUUAAGUUGUAAACGUCUUUUUAAGCCUUUGAAGUGCCUCUGAUUCUAUGUAACUUGUUGCAGACUGGUGUUAAUGAGUAUAUGUAACAGUUUAAAAAAAAAGUUGGUAUUUUAUAAGCACAGACAAUUCUAAUGGUAACUUUUGUAGUCUUAUGAAUAGACAUAAAUUGUAAUUUGGGAACAUAAAAACUACUGAAUAAAUCAUGUGGCCUAAUAUUGAAAAUGUCACUGUUAUAAAUUUUGUACAUUUUUGAUCAAAUGUACAUCUCCCCUUUGCUAACGGCCGUCUGCUCUCAAGGAUGACGUGGGUUUGAUUUCUAAGUGUUUCACAGUGUCUGUAAAUCAAGACCAAAGAGCCUGUCGAUGAGACUGUUUAUUACCAGAUUCACUUCUGAAUUGGCCAGAGGAAAUCUGAAUGUAUUAUCCUGUGUGUGUCUAGGUAGAGAUAUUGGAAGGCUGCCAGGGGAUUUCGAAGUUUGCAACCUUUAUAGGAUAACUGAUGGCAAUAUUAAGACAGACGCCUGCUUUUGCAAAUAACUUACAAGACUGUAAAUUCCAAAGAUCUGAAUGGGGCUUUCCUGAUGUUGGUAUCUAAGGCUUAGGCCUAUAGAUUGAUUUACCUUUGGAAUUGUGCUCCAAAUGUCUACUGAAGCUUAACCGAAGAACUAAUAAAUGGACUACAGUAGCUCACGUUACAGGGAAGGAGGGUAGGCAGGGAGGCUCUGUGUGUUAAAAUGAGGGUCUCACUGCUUUAGGAUUGAAGUGGCUGGAAAGAGUGAUGCCUGGGGAAGGAGAUGGAGUUAUGAGGGUACUGUGGCUGGUACUUUCUGUACUAAACAUUUCCUUUUUCUAUUUUACCACUAAUUUUGUUUUAAACUGUGAGCCGUCCAAGUCAGAAGAAGACAGCAAAAAAAGCAACUUUUCCAACAUACAAUUUACUUUUAAUAAAGUAUGAAUAUUUCAUUUUGAGAACAUUCCCUGGAAUUGCCACAUAAUUCAUUAAAAACAUUUUUUUAAGCAACACUUGGAACAGUGUUUACUUUAAAUCCUUAAUGGCCUUAAUUAAUUCUCAGAUUCCUGCCCCAUCACUUACAGAACCAAUUCACUUUAGAGUGACUAAAAGGAAACGAUAGCCUAGCUUUCUAAAGCCACGCUGUGUCCCUCAAUUACAGAGGGUAGGAAUGGGUAUACCUCUAACUGUGCAAAGCAGAGUGAAAUUCAAUUCAUAGAAUAACAACUGCUGGGAAUAUCCGUGCCAGGAAAAGAAAAAUUUCUGGCAAAUAUUUUGUCACUGCUGUAAAGCAAAAUAUUUGUGAAAGUGCCAAAAUAAAGUCUGUCAUGCCAAAAGUAAAUCAUUGUAUAGACUGACA